AUGGAGCGGACGGGAGGAAGGAGCCCUGACGCCGCGGACCCCACGCCUGCCGGCCAGGCAGCGCGGGGACCCGGCCGGGGUGGGGCUAGGGCGGUGCGCCCCGGAGCCUCCAACCUGGACCCCACCCCGGAGGCGCCGCGACCGCGCUCCCGCCGCCUCCAGGAAGGUGCCCGGAUCGCGCCGGCGACCGGAGGACUCUGCGCCCCGCCGCCUCCCACCCUGUCCCGCCCCGCGCCUGUCGGCGACCCCGCGGGGCCGGUCCCCGUCUCCACCUGCAGUCCGGGGCGCGGCGCCCUUGAGGGAAGCGGGGCUCUGGGAUCCCCCGGCCUGGGCGUGGGACACCCCACGGUCCGCACGAACCUUGGUGGCCCGGGCCCCUGCUCCCCCAGAACAGCGCCCAGGUCUCGGAGAAACCCCCCGAAGCCGUGGGCCCAGACGCUCCCGGGGGACCUCGGUGGGACGGGCAGGGCGGGCGCCGCGGGCGAGGGGACGCGCACUGUCCCCGGGCGAACCAGAAACACCCCACACCGGGCACCUCCCCAGGAAUCGCCCACCCACCCCCAUUGUUCUCCACCAGGUUUCACCUUACCACCCUCCCCCCAGGCAUCUCCCCCGUUGCAUCGCCCCCACGCGGGCAUCGCUCCCACCCGGGCAUCUCGGCUCUGUCCUGCCCUGGGGUGGCCGCAGCCCGCGGGGAGGAAGCGCGGCGAGGCGCCCACACCGGGAAAGUGUCUCCGUGACUCUGCGAGGUUACACUCCGGGUGCGUCGCUGCGGGCUCGUGGGCUCGUGGGCUGCAGCCCCCCGCUCCUGUCGGGUGGACGAGCCCCGGGCCCGCGUGGAGCUGCUCGGUCAAGGCCGGCCCGGGAGGGGCGCGGCGCAGGGCGGGCAGGGGCGGGGUCCUAGGUCAACGUCCAGCCCCAGACCCAGCCCCGCCGCCGGAUCCACCGUGCCUCUGUUUCCCCAUUCCUGAGAAAUCGGAACGCCGGCGGCACCCCCUUCUCCGGGCCGGAGCCUGCGCCCUCCGGAUUGCGCGCCUCUGUCCAGGCGGCGGCCGGGGGUGGGAGCGCGCAGCGGGCCAACUUCCCUAAAGGGAACUGUCGGGAGGGCGCCCAGAAGGGAAAGACCAGGAAGCGCUGGGUGCUGAGCUGGAGUCUGGCCCCUUCCUGGGGGACCGGGGAGGGGGCUGAAGGACAAGAGCAAAAAUCACCCCCUGCAGAACCUAGGAGCUACGUGCAGAACUUUACAGAGUUGAGGCAGCGCCGUAGCUGAGGCCUGACUGCUAACCAGGGAGUGGAGCUCUGAGUGCACUCAAGGAACGCAAGGAAGCCAGGCAGGGAGGAAGGGGCCGGCGGAGUCUAACUUCAGCUGCCAUCUUUUUUGGUGGCACAUCUCGUGGUCACAGGUUGUAGGCUGUGUUUCUGGAAGGUUCAGGUACAGCGCAAGAUUCCACUUGUCUACUUGGCUAUCUCUGUGCCUGAGGUGCCAUGAGGCCAACGGACGUCACUCAAAUUCAUGUCCAGCCAAACUCCCACAGCAAAGAAUCCCGAACCGAGGAUGAAGUUCCUCUAGAAAGCAUUCCUAUCUGUGGCAAAGCUGCAGACACCCCGAAACCCAUCUCCCACCUCGUCUGGAAUUUCAGGAGCUUCGUUUGCUGAGCCAGUGCACUCAUGGCAACCCUGCAGGAAGCCAUGUGGCACCUCUGGGCUUUGCACCGUGUGUGUUCUCUUCUCUAAACUGCUGUUUUUGCUUAGCAAAGAGCCUCGCCUGCCACUGAUGAUGGCAGUGUGGGGUCAUUUUGAAUGGCUGCCUGACACUGCAUGGCACAUUCACGUACACAGUCCUGUGGGAUCGUGACAUAAUAAGAAAUAGAUAUUUCAUCUCUGCCCCUGGUUCCUGACACAGAGCUCCUAAAACCAUUGAAAUUUCCUGGAUAAUAGGAGCUUCUUCUGUUCCAAUGGGGUGACUCUUGGUGGGCUCCUGGAUGGGGGCUGGUCACUAGCGAGACCACACCAUGAUGAGAAACCUGGAGCUUCAGCCCUACCCCCACCUCUGAGCAGGGGAGACGGGCUAGCUAGAGGCGCGGUUCCUAAUGCGCCAUAUGCCUACAUGAAGACGUCUCCGUAAAAGUCCCUCAGCAGUGGGGGUUUGGAGAGCUCCCAGGUUGGUGAACACAUCUCUUUGUGGGGGGCGUGGAGCACCCCAGCUCCCCAGGGCUGGCAGCUCCUGUGCUGAGAACGCUUCUGGACUUCGCCUUACGCACCCUUCAUCUGACUCCUCAUCCCUAUCCUUUAUCGUAUCUUUUAUAAUAAACAUGUUUCUCGCCAGGC